ACGCGGAAGUCAGGUAGGAGCACCCGCCGCUGGCAGCCACUCUCCUGGCCGCCAAACCCCAGCUGGAACUCCGGCCACAGCCAGCAUGCAGGGCGAAGAGAGCCUCCGGAUCCUGGUGGAGCCCGAAGGGGACAGCUUCCCGCUGAUGGAGAUCAGCACCUGUGAGACCGAGGCCUCCGAGCAGUGGGACUAUGUCCUCGUGGCCCAACGUCACACCCAGAGAGACCCCCGGCAGGCGCGGCAGCAACAGUUCCUGGAGGAGCUCAGGAGAAAGGGCUUCCACAUUAAGGUGAUCCGGGACCAGAAACAGGUCUUCUUUGGGAUCCGUGCUGACAACAGUGUCUUUGGCCUGUACCGCACUCUCCUCCUGGAGCCUGAGGGGCCUGCCCCCCACGCCGAGCUGGCCGCGCCGACCACCAUCCCGGUCACCACGAGUCUCAGAAUCCGAAUCGUGAACUUCGUUGUCAUGAACAACAAGACCUCGGCUGGUGAGACCUUCGAGGAUCUGAUGAAGGACGGGGUCUUUGAGGCCAGGUUCCCCCUGCACAAGGUGAGGGGUGGGCUGGCCUGGAGAGGGCCCUGGGGUGGGACCCUGGGAUGGGGGCUCUCACUCUCUGUCACCCGAGCCAGGGGGAGGGACGCCUGAAGAAGACGUGGGCGCGGUGGAGACACAUGUUCCGGGAGCAGCCAGUUGAUGAAAUCAGGAACUACUUUGGGGAAAAGGUGGCCCUGUACUUCGUCUGGCUGGGCUGGUACACCUACAUGCUGGUGCCGGCCGCCCUGACGGGCCUCUUAGUCUUUCUGAGCGGAUUCUCGCUGUUUGAGGCCAGCCAGAUCAGCAAGGAGAUCUGUGAGGCCCACGACAUCCUCAUGUGUCCCCUCGGCGACCACAGCCGCAGGUACCAGCGGCUCUCGGAAACCUGCACUUUUGCCAAGCUCACCCACCUCUUUGACAAUGAUGGCACGGUGGUGUUCGCCAUCUUCAUGGCUCUCUGGGCCACGGUGUUCCUGGAGAUCUGGAAGCGGCAGCGCGCCCGCGUGGUCCUGCACUGGGACCUGUACGUGUGGGACGAGGAACAGGAGGAAAUGGCACUUCAGCUCAUUAACUGCCCCGACUACAAGCUCCGGCCAUACCAGCACUCCUACCUACGCAGCACCGUCAUCCUCGUCCUGACCCUGCUCAUGAUCUGCCUCAUGAUCGGCAUGGCCCACGUCCUGGUGGUCUACCGCGUCCUGGCCUCCGCGCUCUUCAGCAGCUCGGCCGUGCCCUUCCUGGAGGAGCAGGUGACCACGGCCGUGGUGGUGACCGGGGCUCUGGUGCACUAUGUGACCAUCAUCAUCAUGACCAAGAUCAACAGGUGCGUGGCCCUGAAGCUUUGUGACUUCGAGAUGCCCAGGACCUUCUCGGAGCGAGAGAGCAGGUUCACCAUCCGCUUCUUCACACUGCAGUUCUUCACCCAUUUCUCGUCUCUCAUCUACAUCGCCUUCAUCCUGGGCAGGAUCAACGGCCACCCCGGGAAGUCCACGCGCCUGGCGGGCUUGUGGAAGCUGGAAGAGUGCCACGCCAGCGGCUGCAUGAUGGACCUCUUCGUGCAGAUGGCCAUCAUCAUGGGCCUGAAGCAGACGCUCAGCAACUGCGUCGAGUACCUGGUCCCGUGGGUGACCCACAAGUGCCGCUCUCUGCGGGCCUCCGAGUCCGGGCACCUGCCCCGGGACCCCGAGCUCAGGGACUGGCGGCGCAACUACCUUCUGAACCCGGUCAACACCUUCAGCCUGUUCGACGAGUUCAUGGAGAUGAUGAUCCAGUACGGCUUCACCACCAUCUUCGUGGCCGCCUUCCCGCUGGCGCCGCUGCUCGCGCUCUUCAGCAACCUCGUGGAGAUCCGCCUGGACGCCAUCAAGAUGGUCUGGUUGCAGCGGCGCCUGGUGCCGCGCAAGGCCAAGGACAUCGGGACCUGGCUGCAGGUGCUGGAGACCAUCGGUGUGCUGGCGGUCAUUGCCAAUGGGAUGGUCAUUGCCUUCACAUCUGAGUUCAUCCCCCGAGUGGUCUACAAGUACCGCUAUAGCCCAUGCCUGAAAGAAGGCAACUCUACUGUCGACUGCCUCAAGGGCUACGUCAACCACAGCCUGUCCGUCUUCCACACCAAGGACUUCCAGGACCCUGAUGGGAUUGAGGGCUCAGAAAACGUGACUCUGUGCAGAUACAGGGACUACCGCAAUCCCCCCGAUUACAACUUCUCCGAGCAGUUCUGGUUCCUCCUGGCCAUCCGCCUGGCCUUCGUCAUCCUCUUUGAGCACGUGGCCUUGUGCAUCAAGCUCAUCGCCGCCUGGUUCGUGCCCGACAUCCCUCAGUCGGUGAAGAACAAGGUUCUGGAGGUGAAGUACCAGAGGCUGCGUGAGAAGAUGUGGCAUGGAAGGCAGAGGCUGGGUGGGGUGGGGGCAGGCUCUCGGCCCCCAAUGCCUGCCCAUCCCACCCCAGCAUCCAUCUUCAGUGCCAGGAGCACAGACGUGUAGGGCCAGAGCCCGUCCAGAGGCCACCAGGAGCUGAGACAGUGCCACCACCAGCACCUCCCACAAGCCCACCGCUGUGCGUGUUGAGGGGUGCUGUGAGAAGGCUGUGCCCAUGUGGGGCCGCAGGAAUCCCCUGUAUGUUCAGGGCUGUGAGCUGCCACCCUAUUCCGCCUGCUCCGUCUUUGUGGGGGCUCUCAGGCUUGGCACAGCCCUGACUUGAACUCUGGGUGACCCUGGGCACCCACAGAACUGGGAGUGAGGGCUCCUCAGGCAGCCACAAGGCAGGAAAACUGGCGCAAAUUUCCUGGGCCUCCCUCUGACUUCUGGGCGCCAGAUCCUGCCGUGCCCCCAUCCUGGCUGUUGGGGGUGUCCUGAGCCCACCUCGCUGGCCUGUUCCCUUCAGCCAACCCGUUUCUGCAGUAAAAUUAAGCCUGUC